AGACCUUUGUUCUCUGACCACUUGAUAAUGUCAGGACGCGGCAAAGGAGGUAAGGGCCUGGGGAAAGGGGGUGCCAAGCGCCACCGCAAGGUGCUGCGCGACAACAUCCAGGGUAUCACCAAGCCAGCCAUUCGGCGCCUUGCUCGCCGCGGCGGCGUGAAGCGCAUUUCUGGCCUCAUCUAUGAGGAGACCCGCGGAGUGUUGAAGGUGUUCCUGGAGAACGUGAUCCGGGACGCCGUGACCUACACGGAGCACGCCAAGCGCAAGACGGUCACCGCCAUGGACGUGGUCUACGCGCUCAAGCGCCAGGGCCGCACCCUCUAUGGCUUCGGCGGCUAAAUGGCAUUUUGAAGCCCAGUCAUUCUCUAAAAAGGCCCUUUUUAGGGCCCCUAAGCUU